CUCUUCCUGCUCUCCAUCAUGGCGCAGGAUCAAGGUGAAAAGGAGAACCCCAUGCGGGAACUUCGCAUCCGCAAACUCUGUCUCAACAUCUGUGUUGGGGAGAGUGGAGACAGACUGACGCGAGCAGCCAAGGUGUUGGAGCAGCUCACAGGGCAGACCCCUGUGUUUUCCAAAGCUAGAUACACUGUCAGAUCCUUUGGCAUCCGGAGAAAUGAAAAGAUUGCUGUCCACUGCACAGUUCGAGGGGCCAAGGCAGAAGAAAUCUUGGAGAAGGGUCUAAAGGUGCGGGAGUAUGAGUUAAGAAAAAACAACUUCUCAGAUACUGGAAACUUUGGUUUUGGGAUCCAGGAACACAUCGAUCUGGGUAUCAAAUAUGACCCAAGCAUUGGUAUCUACGGCCUGGACUUCUAUGUGGUGCUGGGUAGGCCAGGUUUCAGCAUCGCAGACAAGAAGCGCAGGACAGGCUGCAUUGGGGCCAAACACAGAAUCAGCAAAGAGGAGGCCAUGCGCUGGUUCCAGCAGAAGUAUGAUGGGAUCAUCCUUCCUGGCAAAUAAAUUCCCGUUUCUAUCCAAAAGAGCAAUAAAAAGUUUUCAGUGAAAUGUGCAAUUCUGUUGUGUGUUCUGUGAAAGGAUCCUGGCCAUAUUCAAGUCCUUGGACCUCAAGCCACUUAAAGCUUCGAUGGGAGUAGCUGGUAACAACCCCGUCAUCCUCUGAUUGGAUGCCAGUAUUUCCUGGCAGAUCCAAGUCCAAGCUUCAUAGCAUUCAUUGCCUGUGCUUGCCACACCUUGGUUGAUGUGCUGUGGUGCAGUAGCCCCAUUUGGAGGGGAGGGUUUGGUUGAUGUUGGGGUUUGAAUUUAGAGCCUUGGUUAAGCAGGGUGCAGUGCUCCUGUGUUCCAGGAGGCCCCCUGCUAUUCAGUGAUUCUGUUCUGUACUAGAAAUUUUAUCAGCAUUGAUGCGUCAUGAAGGAAUGACAGGCUUUGGUGUGAUGGUUGAGAUUAAAUUUAGACUUAACUGUU